AGCCGGCGCUCCCGUUACGCCGCGGAGCCGGGAGCCGGAGCCCGAGCCCGCGGCGGCGGCGGGAGGCGGCGAGGGGGCGCCGCGGCGGCGGCGGUGGGGCCUGCGGGGCGGGCGGCCGGGCCCGGCCAGGCCGCGAUGGCGACCAAGAAGGCAGGCUCGCGGCUGGAGACGGAGAUCGAGCGCUGCCGCUCCGAGUGCCAGUGGGAGCGGAUCCCUGAGCUCGUCAAGCAGCUGUCGGCCAAGCUCAUCGCCAACGAUGACAUGGCAGAGCUUCUCCUCGGGGAGUCGAAGCUGGAGCAGUACCUGAAGGAACACCCCCUGAGGCAGGGGGCCAGUCCCCGAGGCCCCAAGCCCCAGCUGACUGAGGUCCGCAAGCAUCUGACCGCCGCCCUGGACCGAGGGAACCUUAAGUCAGAAUUCCUACAAGAAUCCAAUCUGAUCAUGGCCAAGUUGAAUUAUGUGGAAGGUGAUUAUAAAGAAGCUCUGAACAUUUACGCCCGGGUGGGCCUGGACGAUCUGCCACUGACAGCUGUCCCGCCCUACAGGCUGCGGGUGAUCGCAGAAGCCUACGCUACCAAAGGACUUUGUUUGGAGAAGCUGCCUAUUUCUUCUUCUACCAGUAAUCUCCAUGUGGACCGGGAACAGGAUGUCAUCACCUGUUAUGAGAAAGCAGGGGACAUCGCACUCCUGUAUCUCCAAGAGAUAGAAAGGGUAAUACUUUCUAAUAUUCAAAACAGAAGCCCUAAGCCUGGCCCUGCUCCCCACGAUCAAGAACUAGGUUUUUUCCUAGAAACAGGACUUCAGAGAGCCCAUGUCCUCUAUUUCAAAAAUGGGAACUUGACAAGAGGAGUCGGAAGAUUUAGAGAGCUUCUCAGAGCAGUUGAAACAAGAACGACUCAAAACCUGCGAAUGACAAUAGCCAGGCAGCUGGCAGAGAUCUUGUUGCGGGGUAUGUGUGAGCAGAGCUACUGGAACCCUCUGGAGGAUCCACCGUGCCAGUCACCUCUGGACGAUCCUCUCCGCAAAGGAGCAAACACAAAAACCUACACUCUCACUCGGAGAGCCCGUGUCUACUCAGGAGAGAACAUUUUUUGUCCUCAAGAAAAUACGGAAGAAGCCCUGUUGUUAUUGCUGAUUAGUGAAUCAAUGGCCAACCGGGACGCUGUGCUGAGCAGGAUACCUGAACACAAGAGUGACCGCCUCAUCAGUCUGCAGAGUGCAUCUGUGGUCUAUGACUUACUCACCAUUGCUCUUGGAAGAAGAGGCCAGUAUGAGAUGCUGUCAGAGUGCCUAGAAAGAGCCAUGAAGUUUGCCUUUGAGGAAUUCCACCUGUGGUACCAGUUUGCUCUGUCCCUGAUGGCUGCUGGAAAAUCUGCCCGUGCCGUGAAGGUGCUGAAAGAGUGUAUCCGCCUGAAGCCAGACGAUGCCACCAUCCCUCUCCUCGCUGCCAAGCUCUGCAUGGGCUCCCUGCACUGGUUGGAAGAGGCUGAAAAGUUUGCCAAAACUGUCGUUGAUGUGGGAGAGAAAACGUCAGAGUUCAAGGCCAAAGGCUACUUAGCUCUGGGGCUCACGUACAGUCUGCAGGCCACUGACGCUUCUUUGCGAGGGAUGCAGGAGGUCCUACAGAGAAAGGCGCUUCUUGCAUUUCAGAGGGCCCACAGCCUGUCACCCACAGAUCACCAAGCAGCUUUCUACCUGGCUCUGCAGCUUGCCAUCUCCAGACAGAUCCCAGAGGCUCUGGGGUAUGUCCGCCAAGCUCUUCAGCUUCAAGGUGACGAUGCCAACUCCCUGCACCUCCUUGCCCUCCUGCUGUCAGCACAGAAGCAUUACCAUGACGCUCUGAACAUCAUCGACAUGGCCCUGAGUGAAUACCCAGAAAAUUUCAUACUACUGUUUUCCAAAGUGAAGUUGCAGUCACUCUGCCGAGGCCCGGACGAGGCACUGCUGACUUGUAAGCACAUGCUGCAGAUAUGGAAAUCCUGCUACAACCUCACCAACCCCAGUGAUUCUGGACGUGGGAGCAGCCUCUUAGAUAGAACCAUUGCUGACAGACGACAGCUUAAUACAAUUACUUUGCCAGACUUCAGCGAUCCCGAGACAGUGUCAGAUUCCUCCUCCUCCUCCUCUCCUCUUUCAAGAACCGAAUCUCCUCUCCACCUGUUUGUGUCUUCUCAUCUUCAUUCUCCCAAACCCGAUACCUUUGUGUGGCCCCCUGCAGCUCAUUCAUUCAGUGACGCAGGUCCCCGCCGGGAACCCUCUCUCUGCAACUCUCCAGAAGCAUACUUUCAUGGUUUUCCUUCCCUUUUUUCAGUUAGCUCCGUCCAUGCCACAUCGGUAGCAGCCUCAAGAGUGGAGCAGGCACUGUCGGAAGUGGCUUCGUCUCUGCAGAGCAGUGCCCCUAAGCAGGGCCCGCUGCACCCCUGGAUGACGCUGGCACAGAUCUGGCUCCAUGCAGCUGAAGUCUAUAUCGGCAUCGGGAAGCCUGCAGAAGCCACAGCCUGUACCCAAGAAGCUGCCAACCUCUUCCCAAUGUCCCACAAUGUCCUCUACAUGCGCGGCCAGAUUGCUGAGCUCCGGGGAAGCAUGGACGAGGCGCGGCGGUGGUAUGAAGAGGCCUUAGCCAUCAGCCCCACCCACGUGAAGAGCAUGCAGCGACUGGCCCUGAUCCUUCACCAGCUAGGCCGCUACAGUCUGGCGGAGAAGAUCCUCCGGGACGCGGUGCAGGUGAACUCGACAGCCCACGAGGUCUGGAACGGGCUGGGCGAGGUCCUCCAAGCUCAGGGCAACGAUGCGGCGGCUACGGAGUGCUUCCUGACAGCCUUGGAGCUGGAGGCCAGCAGCCCCGCCGUGCCCUUCACCAUCAUCCCCCGCGUGCUCUGAGCAGGCGCCUGCCAGCCUCACCUGCCGCUCAGGCCUCAGAGGCCCUGCCGGGCACCAGGGCUUGUGCCAUCGCCCCAAGGGGAUGAAUCUGCCACACUGAGGCCAGGGACGAGUGUUCAGUGGGCCACAGUGAACCAACCAAACCAACCCCGAAUCAUCGCUCUCGCCAUGUGCGUUUCUCUUGUUUUUUUUGCCAGCCCAAUGGUAGUUUCUGAACCUAUUGACAUUGUUCAAAAUGGAUCAUGUGCCAUAUUUUGUUAGUUGACAUCUGAGUUUUCAGUAAAAUGAUUAUGGAAUUAAUCAGCAAAUGUAGAAGAAUAUAUUCAAAGUUAAAAUUCAGUGGCAGCACAGAUUAUUUUUAUCAGAGCUGUAAAGAAAACAACUGUCCUUUUCUCCCCACCACCCCUCCUGCCCCACUUUGGCCCAGAAACCAAAUGUGAACUUCCUGUCUCCCACCUCAGCACUAGUCCAUGCCAGGACACCAGCUGACAAUUUCUUGGUUUUACUGUCAAUAAUUGUACCAUGUGAUCAAUUACUGUCCUCACUUAGAACAAAGCCUGAGUCCGAGAAUAUUUAUAUUUUACCAAUAUAUGCCUGUUACAAGAGAAGGAAAUAUGAGUUAUUUAAGUUUAACUUUUUUAUGUGAAUUCAGAGUUUAUUUAUCGAGGGAAAUAUGUACAAAGAAGCUUCAAAUGGAAUAUUUACCGACAUUCCUUAUACAUGACAGACACUUGGCUACAUGGGAAGAUGAUGUUAAUAAUAAAAUGAUUUUUAAAUGGACUCAUAGCCUGUGUCAUUCGUAAAAGCUCAAAGACCUGAGAAAGGCUUAGUUCCUGGGGUGGGGAGCUGUCUGUACCUGGGGGCCCACUCUGGACAUGUCAGCCCUUGACACUAGAAAGCCCAGCCUCUCUUUCCCCACUUAUUUUAUUUUUAUUUUUUGGAGACAGGGUCUCACUCUGUUUCCCAGGCUGGAGUUCAGUGGUGCGAUCACAGAUCACUGCAGCCUCGACUUCCCAGGUUCAGGUGAUCCUCCCACCUCAGCCUCCUGAGUAGCUGGGAUCACAGGCGCACACUAGCAUGCCCGGCUAAUUUUGUUUGUUUGUUUUUGUAGAGACGGGAUCUCACUGUGUUACCCAGGCUGGUCCUGAACUCCUGGACUCAAGCAGCCCUCCCGCCUCAGCCUCCGAAAGUGCUGGUGUGAGCCACCAUGCCCGGCCAUCUCCUCACUUAUAAUUUGAAGAUGAUCCCUAGGUAGGGACGUGUUUCCUGCGUCCUCAGCACCCAGGCCUCCUUUUUGCAGCAACAGCCCUGGUUUUGGUUUGGGAAUUCGCCUUAGCUCUCCCCCGAUGGGGCUUUGGAAUUGGAGCAUGCAAUUCAGUCCUGCCCAAGCAGCCUCCUGCACUCAUGGGCCACAGAGGGUCAGGAGUGAGCAUGUGACCUAAAGCGGUCCAGUCAGAGCGGGAGCCACAGAGAAGGCUGUCGCUCUUUCCUGCUGCCUUUCAAGCUGAGAAGUGAGGCUGGAACUGCAGCAGCCCUCUUGCCACCAUGAGAAGAAGGUGUAGAGGUGUUUGAGCCAAAGUCCGAAUCCCACAGAGUAGACAGCAAGAUCCGGAACCAGAGAGAAACUGAGCAGGUAUCUGCAGUCUCUCAGGGACAGCUGUAGGGUGGCCCCACCUUUCCAGGACACAGGGAAAUAUGGAGGGCUGAGCUCUGAACUUAGGUGCCCUGAAGCCUAGAGGACUGCAUUCAAACUGGGCACGACCUCUCUGGCUCACUGAGGCAGGCGGGCUAGGGGGCAGCCAAGGAGGGAGAGACAGUAGGUAGGAGCCCCAGCCUCAGCACUGACCCUGCCAGGCAGCACUUGUGGCUUUGAGUGGUCAUAAGUCAUGGAAUUUGCAAUGUAGGACCUGGGGCAGGUACUCAGUGUGGUGGCAGCUUGCCCUGAUUGGAGGCACAGGGCUGGGCUCUGCCAUCCCAUGCGGGAGCGUGGGGCAAGGCCCACUGGAUCAGGACCAGGAAGGGAGGAGGCUGGGCCACCAAGGCAGAUGGUGCAGGCGCUGUACCAGACCUUCUCUGCCAGGCCCUCACCUCAGAGACUCCUGUGCGUAUCAGCCCUGCAGGGCGCGGGGGCUGGCUCCUGUGUGUCUGCCCGGCACCUCUCCAUUGUCUUCAUCUCCCUCAGGGAACCACCCCCACUCUCCACCCACAUGGCUCAAGGAUGGACACAUGGGCCCAGCCUUAACAACCAGAGCCCUCCAGCUCCCCAGUAUCAGUGACUGGUUUGGGUUUGGGCAUGUGACCCAUGCUUGGCCAAUGAGAAGCACCCCUGGGACUUUUGUUAUGAAAACAUUAGAAAAAAAGCCUCUUUCUGCUGGGUUUGAUGUCCUAAUAGGAUGCCAGUGGGGGGCUGUGGGUGCCAUUUGACAUUAUAUGGGGUGGCCUGCCUGAGAAUGAUGCCAACACAGAAAAAGAGAAUGAGGAGGUGGAAAGAGAGCCGGGCCCCGGGUCACCGCUGGAGCACUGCGGCCCGAGAUUUUUCCAUCAUAGGAAUCCAUACAGUUUCCCAUCUUGCUUAGUGCAAGCACAGGGGUUUCCAUCACUUCUACCUAAAAGGUACCUAAGAAAUGCAGGAAAGUCCUGCCGUCCUUGGUACUCCCCCCUUGGGCACUCUUCCAGACUCCUCAGUCCCCCACCUUAAUCCCACUCACCCACCUCAUAUUCUGUUUUCCAGUAAAUCUUGUCUUUUCUACCCAAAUCGCAUCUCAAAUCUCUCCCAUUCAACUUCAUCCCCAGUACCUUGGCCCCAGCCCCACACAGUCCAAUGUCUGCACAGUCCUCUUAGAAGGGAGGAUUGAGUCGGUUCUCUCUAUAAACCCCUGAUGGCUUCUCAAGCCCUUGCCUGGAACCAGACUCUGUGUCCCAGCCCCCUGUGUGCCUGGCUGCCUCUCCUUCCCCAAGCCCUCUCAUGGCUCUGGCCUUCUUCCUAGUCUUCUGACCUGCUGAGCCUUUCCCAACUAAGGACAUUCAUCCAUCCGUCCAUCCAUCCAUCCAUCCAUUCAUCCGUCCACCCGUCCGUCCGUCCGUCCAUCCAUCCAUCCAUCCAUCCAUCCAUCCAUCCAUCCAUCCGUCCAUCCAUUAAUAGAUGAGGACGCAGACGCUAGACACUAAGACGGCAGGACACCUGCCUGGGGUCAUUGUGGAAUUACCUGGCAGAACUAAGAUUGAGACAGGCCUGAGGGAUAAACAUUUCAAAAGUGCCCAGGUCUGCCCAGUGGAGGCAUUUUUUGGACAGUGAGAUGCAGGAGAUGCCGCGUUUGAUUCCAGGACUAGUGCUGACCCUAACUUAGGCAAGGCGUUCCUGUUCCCUGGUCUUAGUCUCCCCAUCUGUGAAAUUUCAUUCAUUCAUUCACUCAUUCAUUCAUCCAACAAAUAUCUAUGGAAUGCUCACAACAUGCCAGAUGCUUAUUCCAGGCACUGAGGGCACAGCAAUGUGUGACACAGAUGCUGCAUCCACUUAGGACCUACCUUCUGGUAGAAGGAAACAGACAGAUGAGGAGUAUGGCAGGUGGGGUGACGCAUGGAGAAAGAUGAAGCCAGGGAAGGGGUGUAGGGAGUGGCAGGGCUGCUGUUUAGAAGGUGACUAGGGAAGCCUCGCUAAGAAGGUGACAUCUGGCUGAAGAAAGACAGGUAACCUGGGAGGAGGACAUCUCAGGAAGCAGGAACAGCAGGUGCAAAGGCCCAGAGGGGAGGGGGAUGGUCAGGUGGUGAAGGAUGAGAAGAGGUCAGAAGUUUAACAGGGGCCACACAGGUGCGGCCUCGUGGACCAUGCUAACAGUGUAUAUUAAUUGCCUGUGGUUGCAGCAAAUUACCAUAAACUGGCUGGGCAUGGUGGCUCCUGCCUGUAAUCCCAGCACUUAGGGAGGCUGAGGCAGGAGAAUCAGCUGAGGCCAGGAGUUCAAGACCAGCCUGGGCAACAUGGUGAGACCCCCCCCCCAUCUCUACAAAAAAAAAAAAAUAGCCAGGUUUGGUGGCGUGCACCUGUAGUCCCAGCUGCUUGGGAGGCUGAGAUGGGCUGAUUGCUUGAGCCCAGGUGGUUGAGGCUGCAGUGAGUGAUCACGCCACCGCAGUCCAGCCUGCAUGAGAGAGCAAGACCCUAUCUCUACAAAUAAAAUAAAUUAAAAAUUUUAAAUGACCGCAAACUUAGCGUCUUAACACAAAUUUAUUCUCUUUGUUUUGGAGGUCAGAAGUCAAAUCAAGCUUUCAGUGGGGCUGUGCUCCUUCCCCAGGCUCUGGAGGAGGACGGGUGUCCCCGUCUUCUCCAGCGGCUAGAGGCUUCCUGCGGCCUUGGCUCGUGGCCACCUCACGUCACCUUUCCUUCCUCUGCUCCGUCACUGCGUCACCUUUCUGCCUUUGACCUCCUGCCUCCCUCUAAGGACUCUGCUGGUUGCUCUGGGCCCCCUGGAUAGUCCAGGGCCAUUGCCCCACCUCGAGAGCCUUCGUUCAAUCACAUCUGCAUCGCUCCAUCUGUCAUGGAAGGCAACAUAGUCACAGGUUCCAGGGCUCGGGAUGUGGACGUCUUUGAGGGGCAGGGGGAGCACGUUAUUCUGCAGGCCGCAGCGUGGGAGCUGGGAGGCUGUCAGGCUCCUGCUGUCACACAGCGACCAUGGUGCUUAGACCAAGGGGCGUGGAGGAAGUGGCGAGAGGCACUGGACUGUGAAGAUUCUGAAGACAGAGCCAAGAGGGUUGCUCACACAUGGAGCUGGGUGUGAGGGAGGGGAGACGCCAGGGAUGAGGGUGAGGGUCUUGUCCUGAGCUACUGGAAGGAUGGCGAUGAUGGCCAGGAAACAGGAAGAAUAGGUUGGGGAGGAGAGGAGAAGGCAGGAGUCUGCUUUCAGGCAGGUUGAAUACAAAAUGCCUGUGGAGCCUCUGAGGGGGAGGCAGCUGGCUGGGCAGGAGCCCAGGCGAGAGCCCAAGAUGAGGCGAGAGUGUGGGAGGUGUCAGGGAUGCGGGGCUGGGAGCCAUGGGCCUGACGGGGCCACUUCGGGACAAGCAUAGACAAAGAGGAAGAGGUCAGGGCUGAGCUCCGGGGCUGGCGGGGUUUACAGGCUGGGAAAUGAAGAGAUCAGGAAAGAAGGCGCAGGAGCAGCUGCAAGGGAGGCGGAGAGCAGGCAGGGUGAGCUUCCUGGAGGAGGUGGGUGGGCUCUCUCAAUGCCUGGAGACCCCGUCAGGGUGGCCUGAGAGCUGACCGUGGGCCUGGUGGUGUGCAGGUUGGCAGUGACCUUGACCAGAGCCAUGCUGGGGAUGCAGUUUUGCUCCCCCAGAUUCAUAGGGUGGAGCCCCCGCCCCUGUGUGACUAUAUUUGGAGAUAGGCCCCUUAAGGAAGUAAUUCAGGUGAAGUGAGGUCAUCAGGAGGGGCCCUGGCCCAGUAGGAUUGGCGUCCUCACCAGAAGAAACUCUAAAGUGCAAGUGAGCUCACGCUCAGCCACGCCAGGACACACGGAGAAGGCGGCCACCCGCAAGCCAGGAGGGAGCCUCACAGGAACCCAGAUGGGCUGGAACCUUUGCUUUGUUCUUUGAACCUCCAGGACUGUGAGAAAUUAAGUUCAUUGUUGAAGCCACCUGUCUGUGGCGGUUUUCUUACGGCAGCCCAAGCUGACUAAGGUGGGGUCAAGCCAGGUUGGAGUGGGCUCAAGGGGGAGGAAAAGGUGAAGUCUCUUUCAAGAGCGUAGCUGCAGAGGGGAGCUGAGAACACAGGUUAGGAGUCCGGUGGGGAAGGGGCCGUGUUGAGUGUUGAAGGCGGCCUCGCUGAGCACCUUGUGUUUCCAGCAGGGCAGGCGUGAGGAAGGAGAGAGGGAAGCUGAGGGGGGCUGCCUUGGCUGGGGGCCUGGUGGUUCCCCAGAGCAGCAGCAGCAGGGAGGCAGAGGCCUGGGUACCCCCAAGCCAGGGAGCCCUGGGGACGGGGCACCCACUCCUCAGUGAGCAGGGAGCCAACUUCGGGCAGGGUGGGGUGGCGAAUGGACCAGGAAGGGAAGGAGGAGGCAGAGGAGGGAGGAGGCCCUUCUUUGAAGGAGCCGCCCCACUCAGCCAAGAGGAUCUCAGGACAGAGCCAGGCUGGGGGCCUGGGCAGGUGUGGCCGGGGCAGGCCACUUCCCAUCCCCAGCCCCAUUUGGGAUCCAUGGGCUCGUCUGUCUGUCUCUCUGCCUCCUUCCAGGUCCUGGGCCCUGGGCUGUGGCCAGGGCUCUGCUCACCCUCAGGGCUGCGUGGGGACCUCCCUCGGUGGGGAAAGGAGGGAACCAAGGCCUCCCGUUAUCCUCCAUGCCCCCUACCUGUGGUCAUGGCCUGGGGGAGGUGCAUGCUCGUGCACAGGUGGGCGUGUCUGUGAUCACAUGGAGCAACCCAGACUCCUCCAGAUGGCCCCACGCAUCUCCCCGGCGGCCACACAGUCAUCAUUGCGGGCCCAGACUCUCUGCCUGCAGGAAGUCCCCCCUUUGCAGGCACCCUCCCCAUCAUCCUUGGAGUUCUCCACGUCUGCCCUGUCCGUGCUGGGCCUGUCACCAGCCUGUCACCUGCUGCCCCAGCCCCAGCCCAGGUCCCUGCAGCACAGCCGGCUCCAGGCUGGAAUGGGUGACCCGGCCCUACUGAAGGAAUUUCAGGGCAGGGUCAGCCACUCUGGCCACUGUCUCCCUCCAAUGCCCCCAUACCCUCCCAGCGCUCGGCCCCUGCCACUCGGCCCCCUCUCUCCAUAUCGCCACCUUCUCAUUCCUGCUCCUCCCCCACCACCUCUCAAGGCCGACAGGGUGGGCAUUGCCCAGUGAGGGGACACCACUCAUAUUGAAGUUCUGUAAACUGUGUCUUGGGCACUGUACCAGGUGGCUGCUCCCAUCCCUCCCCUAGCGUCUGCUUGCCCUGUCCAUCCUGCCUACUCCAGAAGCAGCCACACACUUGACCAUAAGCCUUUGAGGCCUGGCCGGAGUCCUCCGGGGGAGGCGGGCAGUAGCAGCCGCACUGGGCCUGAGGACCCCACACAGGAAAAUGGGCCGAGCCCCAGGGCUGAGCCUUAGGGCUGCGGCCGUUCCCGCCACUAACAUUCCUCCCACACUUGUGGUCAUGCAUUUCCUGCUGCCCCUGCCCACGCUGCAGCCAGAUAGGAACAGAAAAAGGACAUCCUGCACCAUUUCAGACAGGAAUGUGCUCCUCCUGAAGGUCUUUUGGGGGCCAGGCUGAGGCCCCCCCUCAAGGUCACACCGUGGGGGACCCACUCCAGCUCUGCACCUGCUGGGGGUGAUCCUCACUGUGCCACUGUCCCUCCCUGGACUCAGAAUCAGAUGAGGACAGUCACCUCUGCCCAGCCUGCCUUCUGGGCUGAGAUGUGAGUCUGCAGGCAGCUGUCAGAGGUGGUGUGUGCCAGGUAGGGGACACGAGGGCUACCGCCCCUCAGGACCACCACACAGGGCCUCAGGGCCAGGCCAGCAGGCAGGACUCCUCCUGGACACUCAAGCCCUGAGUGGGGCUGACUAUGGAGAGGUGGCAGGAAGGUGGUGGGGGAUCUUCUGCAGGUCUGCCUGGAGCCAGCAGCUCCCGCUGACCAUCCGGGCCACCCACAGCCCCCACCACCCUCCUCGUCUCCCUCAUCUUCUGCUGUUUGGCCCUUGACCCCCUGAGGACAAUAGGGUUUCCUGGUGACCACUGGGCUGUGGGUCACACAGAUCUGGCUGGAAUCCCAGUUCUGCCUGGCCGUGUCACCUCUGAUGGGGAAGCACUCUGUCUCCUCAUCUCUAUGGUCGGGGAGUAACUUCCCUUACGGGCUUUUGGGGAUAUUAACAGAGGUCAACCUGGACAGGGCAUGGGGCCCCCGGGGUGCACCAUAAAGUCUUUCCUUCUUUCUUCUAUCCUCAGGCGAGGGGUGAGUGGCUGCUGGGACGUGCUGAGGGGUCCCUGAAGCAGGGCAGGAAGGGCAGAGCUAGCUGCAGCUGAGGCAGAGUCCGAGUCCCGCUCUGCAUGGAGGAGGAGGUGAGGGGCCUGGUCAGCAUGGGCAUGGCUGGGGGCCUCUGUGACCGCCACCACUCUUGUCUUUGCCUCCUUGACCCCACAGGGUCAUCCUCGGGCCCUGGGUCCAGCCAAGGCCUGAGGAGGGUCAUGCAUCCCUGUCCCACUUGGUCACAGCACAGGAGGCUCCCAUCCGCCACUGCCUGAGGCGGUGCCUGUGGCCCAAGGGCUCGGGUUGUGGGCCUGCUGGGCUGGAGCCUGCAUCGGGACCUGGCCACCUACUCUCCUAGGAGCCUUAGGUGAGUCACUAGUCCUCUCUGAGCCUCGGUUUCCUCAUCUGUGAAAUGGGGAGAACAAGGUGGUUGUAAAGAUUCAGAGGGUGUGUAAAACACAAGCACAUGGCCGAGCACAGCCCAGCCCUACCCCUGCAUGGCUCCUCCCCCGGGCAUGGCAGGAGGUCAGGGUUUCCAGCCUGAGCUUAGCCUGCCAUUCAGCAGUACCCAGGAAGGCACAGCUACCAGGAAAAUGACCUCCCCAAGCCCAUGGAGGCUUCCUGAGCACCCAGCCCAGCCUGAACCUCCACCCACCCAGGUGGCAGUGAGGCCUUCCUGCCUGUGUUCAGCCACGGUGUAUCAAGGACCCCUGGCCAGACACAGGUACCUGGGCUGGGGAGCUGGUGGUCUUAUUGGGGACUGGGAAGACAGACCCCAAACAGAGGGGUAAACAAAUAAGAUAAUUACCAGCUUGGCAGAUGAUUAGAGCAAAUUUGAAGUGACAGGGGGAGGGUUACUUUAGAUUGGCUGGUCGGGGACACCUCUGUAAGACAGUGACAUUGAGUGACAAGAAGGUGCCCACCCUGGAGGACACUGGGCUUCUUCACCUUUAAGAGGGAUGGUGAGCAGAAGCCCAAAAGCGUCAGGUUCUGCCACUUUGUACCAGAUGACUAGGCCCAGCCAGUUUGCAAAAGGGCUGGCCCAUCCUCACAUUGGCCCAUCCUCACAUUGCCAGCAAGGACCAGACCAUGUGAAGAGGGAAGAGCAUCCUGUAAUGUACAAAUAGGGGAUCAACUUUAAAUUAUCUCCAGAGUUUCUUUCUUUAAUAUGUUGUCCAAAGGUAACUAUGUUAAUUUUUACAAAUAUUUUUAUGUAGUUUUAUAUAGUUUUACAAAUAGUUUUAUGUAGUUUUGGUUUUUAUUUGUUUGUUUUUGUUCUACUUGAGAUGGGGUCUUGCUCUGUCACCGAGGCUGGAGUACAGUGGCACGAUCUCAGUUCACUGCAGCCUCCACCUCCCAGGCUCAAGUGAUCCUCCCACCUCAGCCUCCUGAGUAGCUGGGACUACAGAUGCCAAGCCCCACUAAUUUUUUUCAGAGACAGAGUUUUGCCAUGUUGCCUAGGCUGAUCUCCAACUCCUGGUCUCAAGUGAUCUGGUCCCCUCAGCCUCUUAAAGGUCUGGGAUAACAGGUGUGAGUCAGUGUGCCUGGCCUAUGUAGCAGUUUUUAAAACUACAAAAUUAAAUAAGAAAGGGGCAGAGCUCAGACACAAUGAGACUUUUCAGUCCAGUGUUUUCAGAUUCUCUGGCUUUCAACUUUACAAUUUCACUUCAAAAAUUUCAACUUCAAAUUUCACUUCAUUGCUUUCAAAAUCUUGAGCCAGCUUGUCCUUUGGAUCUGGACUGUGCCUGUCUGCACUGGCAGAUGGACAGAGCUCCUGUAUAGAAAUGAAGCCAGUUCACCCACGGCUUUUUUUUUUUUUUUUUUUUUUUUGAGAAGGAGUUUCGCUCUUGUUGUCCAGGCUGGAGCGCAAUGGCACAAUCUCGACUCACUGCAACCUCCGCCUCCUGGGUUCAAGCUGUUCUCCUGACUCAGCCUCCCGAGUGGCUGGGAUUACAGGCAUGCGCCAUCACGUCCAGCUGAUUUUUGUUUUUUGUUUUUUUUUUGUUUGUUUUUUUGUUUUGUAUUUUUGAUUUUUUGUGCUUAGUAGAGACAGAGUUUCACCAUGUAGGUCAGGCUGGUCUCGAACUCCUGCUUCAGGUGAUCUGCCCGCCUCAGCCUCCCAAAGUGCUGGGAUUACAGGCGUGAGCCACUGUGCCCAGCUGUUUUUUUGUUUGUUUGUUUGUUUGUUUAAGCAAGCAGCUUUUUCUUUUCUUUUGUGAUCGUAAAACCUACACCCACUGUAUCAGCUGCCUGUUGCUGCUACAACAAAUUGCCACAAAUAUAGUGGCUUAAAACAGCAUACAAUUUUUUCUUUCUUUUUUAAGUUAUAACAAUAUAUUUUAAUCUCAUAACAACUUCAACUGAAUACAAAACUCUUUACAUUUUCAGCUAUUAAUAUUAAAAUUAUAUCAUUUUAUAUCCUGUAUCUAUUAACAGAGAUUUAUGCAGAUUUACAUUUUGUUCUUCAAAUUCUAUAGAAUUUUAAUUUUUUAUUUUCAUAGGUUAUUGGGGAACACAGUGGUUACAUGAGUAAGUUCUUUAGUGGUGAUUUGUGAGAUUUUGGUGCACCCAUCACCCGAGCAGUAUACACUGCACCCAAUAAAACAACGCACAUUUCCUGUCUUACAUGUAGUUCUGGGGGUCAGAAGUCUAAAACGGGCCUCAUGGGGCAAAAGGCAAGGUGACGGCAGGGCUGUUCUUUCUGGAAGUACUAGGAAAGACAUCAAACUUUGCCCUUUCCAGUUUCUCAGGGGUGUGCUUGGCUCAUGGCCAUGUUCACUGCCGGCAGUGGCAUCACUCCGACCUCUGCUGUAGAGCGAUCUCUGUGACUCCUCCUUCUCUGCCUCUGACCCUCCUGUCUCCCUCUUUCCCUUGUAAGAGCCUCCUGAUUACAUUGGUCUUACCUGGAUAAUCCAAGACACUCUCCCCAUCUGAAGAUCCCUCAUCAAAUGGCAUCUGCACAGCCCCUUUUGCCAGGUAAGUGACCAUCUUCACAGGUUCCAGAAAGUAGGAUGCAGGCAUCUUUUGGGACCAUCAUUUCACUUACCAUAGUCACCUUGGGGACAAUUUCAGACAUACGAAGACUAAGAUCAUUAAAUUCCACUAUUUAGCGCUCACCUUCUCAGCAUUUUGGCCUGUUGUCUUGCAGCAUUCUCCCAUGAGUAUAGAUUUUUUUGUUUUUUGGGAUGGAGUCUCGCUCAAUUGCCCAGGCUGGAGUGCAGUGGUGCGAUCUCGGCUCACUGCAACCUCCACCUCCCGGGUUCAAGUGAUUCUCCUGCCCCAGCCUCCCGAGUAGCUAGGAUUACAGGCACGUGCCACCACGCCUGGCUAAUUUUUUGCAUUUUUAGUAGAGACGGGGUUUCGCCGUGUUGGCCAGGAUGGUCUUGAUCUCCUGACCUCGUGAUCCGCCCACCUCGGCCUCCCAAAGUGCUGGGAUUACUUACAGGCGUGAGCCACAGCGCCCAGCCAAGUAUAGAUAUUUAAUGAAGUGAAAUCAUACUAUCUAUAACACCGUAUGGAUCUUUUCACUUAAUAUUCUCUUGUCAGUAAAAAUCUUUCUAGAUAACUUAGAGACAGCAUAACCUCCCCUCACAUGGAUGCACUGCAGACUGUUUAACCCUUUCUUUAUUGUCAAUGAUUUAAGUGGUUUCACAUUGUCAUGCCACAUACAAUGGAAUGGGUAAUGCCAGCUCACAAUUAUUGAGCAUUUAUUAUGCACCAAUCAUUCGACAUGUAUUAACUCAUCUAAUCCUCAUGACAGUGCUAUGAUAUGCAUACAGUUAUUACGGAUACAGGUCCAGGUGAGAAAUGAAGCUCUCUUCAGAAGAUGAACAAACUUGCCCAAGUUUGGGUAAUACUACAGCAGGCCUUGAACCCAGGUUGCCUGACUCCAGAAUCCAUACUCUUAGCCACUCACAUGCUCAUGUUUUCUCCUAGCAUCUCUGAUUAUCUAUCUUAGGGUAGAAUUCGGAUAGGCAGAAUGGCAGUUCAUCAGGCUAUAUUUAUUGAGGGCUUAGUUUGUGCAUUUUCCAUGGGCUCACUGAGUUAAUCCUCAUGACUCCAAGAAGUGGUCUGUUAACUGGCCGAAGCCACGCUGGUUGGCUCCAGUAGCUAGACUCUGCCUGGAACCUCUGUGUGGUAGCCAGUCAUUAGCGGUGGUGAGGGCUACGGCCUCUCCCUGACAAGCUCACCUUGCCAGACGGUGCCCCCAUGAAUGCAAAAUGCAGUCAGAUCCCGCUAUCGGAAAGAGGUAACAAAGCGCAGUCAGGUCACGCCAUCAGAAACAGGUAACAAAGCGCAGUCAGGUCACGCCAUUGGAAACAGGUAACAAAGCAGUCAGGUCACACCAUCGGAAACAGGUAACAAAGCGCAGUCAGGUCACACCAUUGGAAACAGGUAACAAAGCAGUCAGGUCACACCAUCAGAAACAGGUAACAAAGCUCAGUCAGGUCACGCCAUUGGAAACAGGUAACAAAGCAGUCAGGUCACACCAUCAGAAACAAACAUCAGAAACAGGUAACAAAUCACAGUUGGGUCACACCACCAGAAACAGGUAACAAAGCGUAGUCAGGUCACACCAUCGGAAAUGGGUAACGAAGCGCAGUCAUGUCACACCAUCAGAAACAGGUAACAAAGUGCAGUUGGGUCACACCACCAGAAACAACCAUCAGAAACAGGUAACAAAACACAGUCGGGUCACACCAUCAGAAACAACCAUCAGAAACAGGUAACAAAGCGCAGUCAGGUCACACCAUCGGAAACAGGUAACAAAACACAGUCGGGUCACACCAUCAGAAACAACCAUCAGAAACAGGUAACAAAGCACAGUCAGGUCACACCAUCGGAAACGGGUAACGAGGCACAGUUGGGUCACGCCAUCAGAAACAACCAUCAAAACAGGUAACAAAGUGCAGUCGGGUCAUGCCAUCAGAAACGGGUAACGAAGCGCACUCGGGUCACACCGUCGGAAACAGGUAACAAAGUGGGAGGUCAAGGCUGCAGUGAUUAUGCCACUGCACCCCAGCCUGGGAGACACAGCAAGACCCUGCCUCAAAAGAAUGACAAAAAUAAAAUAAGUUGCUCUACCACUUUGCGUGGUCACCUGCAGAGUGUGAAAGUGUCCACUCACAAUGUGGCCCUGGUUCUUAACUGACCAUUUGGAGGGUUGUCUGUAGCCACUGAAACCCAGACUCCAGCUUCCUCCAGGCUCUCUGUCCGGCUGGACAGAAGGAGGAGCUGGUGCUGCUGUUUAGCCAGCCAGGGGAUUGGAGGCUCACAGCAGGGGAGCGUGGGGCUGUCACCCAUUCCUGUUUCCAUGGUUUGUAUGGGUAACCGGGAGGCAGCAGGCGACCCCAUGGCUAUGUCAUCCACAGAGAGAAACCUUAUCACAUACGGAAGCUCUUAUUCAUACAACAUAUGCCAACCUUGUCAACCAAUAAAUGCCUAUGGAGCCUUUACUCUGGAUCAAGACAUCCUUCCAAGUGAUCCACCCGCCUCAGCCUCCCAAAGUGCUGGGAUUACAGGCGUGAGCCGCCACACCUGGCUCGCCAUUUUCCUUUAGCUUGUGAUGUGAUCAUAAAGUGAGUCACAUCUGCCAGGCGCAGUGGCUCACGCCUGAAAUCCCAGCACUUUGGGAGGCUGAGGUGGGUGGAUCAUGAGGUCAGGAGAUCAAGACCAUCCUGGCUAACACGGUGAAAGCCCAUCUCUACCAAAACUACAAAAAAUUAGCUGGGCAUGGUGGCAGACACCUGUAGUCCCAGCUACUCGGGAGGCUGAGGCAGGAGAAUGGCAUGAACCCGGGAAGCAGAGCUUGCAGUGAGCCGAGAUGGCGCCAUUGCACUCCCACCUGGGCGACAGAGUGAGACUCCAUCUCAAAAAAAAAAAAAAAAAGUGAGUCACAUCUCCCUCUGGAUCUCAGUUUCCUUGUCUGUAAAAAUGGUAAAGAAGGUUUUGACUAAGUGAUCCCUGAGCCUUUGUAACUGCGAAUUUGCUAAGUUUAGAGAUUAUUAGGACUUCUACCAGAGGGACAGUAACAGGGGUGGGGUUAAGUGAAACAUCAAUGUGAAGUGCCUGGCGUAGAAGAUCCUCAGAGUCAAGUGAAGCUUGGGGAGCUUCAUCACUGGAGUGUGGGCUGGACUUGGUGACUUGCAUUCAGAGAGAAGGAUGUGGAAAUAGGAAAAAUAGUAACAUUACCACAGAGAAACCUGGCAGGACAUCACCUUCACCAGUCAAUGAAGGUCAGCAUUCCCAGUGAUGAGUCGUGUGAAUACCAGGUACCCCCAGAUAUGAUGGGGUGAGCAGGGCACCUCAUCUCUGUGGUCUUCUUCCCCCAAACCCAUAACUCCAGUGUAAUCAUGAGAAAACAUCAGACAAACCCAAACCGAUGAACUUUCUACAAAAUACCUGACCAAUACCCCUCAAAACUACCAAGAGCAUGAAAAAGAAAAGUCUAAGAAACUGACGAAAACCAGAGAAGCCCAUGAAGACAUAGCUAAAUAUUAGGUGGUACGGGGUCCUGGAUGAAAGGCACCGUAUUAGUACGUCCUCAUGCAGCUAAUAAAGACAUACCCGAGACUAGGUAAUUUAUAAAGAAAACGAGUUUAAUUGACUCACAGUUCAGCAUGGCUGGAGAGGCCUCAGGAAACUUACAAUCAUGGAGGAAGGGGAGGCAAACAUGUCCUUCUUCACAUGGCAGCAGGAAGGAGAAGUGCCGUGCAAAAGGAGGGGGAAAAACCCUUAUAAAACCAUCAGAGCUCAUGAGAACUCACUAUCAUGAGAACAGCAUGAGGGUAGCCACCCCCAUGAUUCAAUUACCUUGCACCGGGUCCCUCCCAUGACAUGUGGGGAUUAUGGGAACUACAAUUCAAGACGAGAUUUGGGUGGGGACACAGCCAAACCAUAUCAGGCACAUUCGUAUUAUAAGCUGCUGACAUCUAAAUAAAGUCUGGAGUUUGGUUACUAGUAAUUUAUCAAUGUCAGUUCCAUUGUUGGCACAAAUGUGCCAGGUAACAUAAAGGUUAUAUUAGGGGAAAUUGAGUGAAGGGUAAAUGGGAAUUCCCUGUGUUAUCUCUGAAACUUUUCAGUGAAUCUAAAAUUAUCCCAAACUUAAUAGUUUAUUUUUUUUUAAAGUAAGGUCUAGGCCAACAAGCACAUGAAGAAAUGUUCAACAUCAUUACUCACUAGGGAAAUGCAAGUCAAAACUCCAAGAGAUACCACCUUACACCCACUAGGAUGUCUAUAAUCAAAAAGACAGACAAUAACAAAUGUUUGUGAGGACGUGGGGAAAUUGGAACCCUCAUACGUUGUUGGAGGGAAUGUAAAAUGGUACAGCCACUUUGGAAAACAGUUUGGCAGUUUCUUAAAAAGUUAGACAUAGAAUUAUCCAGGAAUUCCUCUCUUAGUAUGUACCCCAGAGAAAAGGAAAUAUAUGUACAAAUAUAAAAUACAAAGACUUCUUUUUUUUUUUUAUUUUUUUUAUUUUUUUUUAUUUUUUAACCAAUCGCAACUCUGUACGUUGGUAUUAUUCUAAGGGAGCAAAGCUUUGCCCCAACCCCCACCCCCAUGUCCUGGUACUCUUCCACUCUGAGAGCUUUAGAACCGGGGUUCCAAAGUCUCUGCUUAGCCUAACAGUGACGUGCUUGUCACAAAGCCAGAGGCCGGUGUACUCGGGUUAGAGAGGGCCUUUGUCGUUGGGUUUUAUUCUUAUUGUAUUAUUCGGGCUCCACCGACCCAAAUAUUAGUCAACUGGGUUGGGCGAGGUAGGACGGAUGAAGCCCACCGUCUAACAAUCUGGACAUCUAUAGGAGCAGAUCCGCCGCUCGAAACAGCUGACCCAGCGACGACUGCGGAACCACUAGCAGCGUCUGCACAGAUCGACCCCGCCAUCCCGCCGUCCCGUUCGGUGACCGGAGACGCAGCCGGGAACGCGACUGAUCAGGCUACCGAGCCGGGCCGCAGGGCGAAAGCGGUGCGGUCCGAGGCCUCAGAAAGGGACACGCAGCAGCGGCAGUGGCGCUGACUCAGCCCGGCCUCCCUGCAGUCCCCUCAAAUACAAAGACUUCUCCGCAAAUGUUUAUAGCAGCUUUAUUUGUAAUAGCCAAAAACUGAUCACAAUCCAAAUGUCCACCAACAGAUCAAAGGAGAAGCGAAUUGUGAUCUGUCCAUAUGAGGGGCUUGGUGCCUGCAGCAACAUGGGUGAAUCUCCAGGUAGUGGUGACGAGUUGAAGGAGCCAGUCAAAAAAGAACGUGCUGUGUGAUUCCAUUUAUAGAAAACUCUAGAAAAUGUGGACUAAUCUAGAGUGAGGGAAAGCAGACCCGUGAUUGCGCCUGGGGCAAGGAGACUUGGGGGUGGAGGGGGGGCCAGAGGGAGGGGUUUCAAAGAUGAUAAAGACAUUUUGAGGGUGAUGGAUAUGAUCCCUCUCUUAAUAGUGGCGAUGGCUUCAUGGAUAGAUACAAAUGUCAAGACAUAUUGAACUGUAUACUUUAAAUGCUUGCGCUUUACUACGUGCCAAUCACAUCUUCAUAAGGCUGUUUUUUGUUUUUUUGUUUGUUUUUUUUUUUUAAAAAAAAAGGCCUCGUAAUGGAGAUGAGUACAGCCUGGCCUCAGUCUCCCCACCUGCAAUGUGGGGGAUCCCCGUGUGCCUUGCACCACCUGAGAGCUCCAGGCUUAGGAGGAGACCGAGGUGAGCCCUGUUUCUAGCCAGAAACCCCAAGGCCCUAACCCCCAGGGCUGGGCAGCUGCAGGGCCCAGGCUACUGCCCCUCCGGGGAUGGACGGUGCGAGGCCACUCCAGGGGCAUGACCUGUUUUGGGCAGGCGGUGGCUGUGGGGAGAAGAGUGGGGAGGUCCCUUUCUUUUUUCUUCCUGAAUAAAAAAAUGCAUGAUGCUA